UUCCGCGCCAUUCAUUCACGCGCGCGUUCGGGCGUUCGUUCCACAAGCGUUUGUAGAAUGUCGACCCGGUCGAGCCGCCGCUCCCACCCGCACUCCAGCCACAGCGUUUUUCCGCACCCCGCCUUCGACGUCCCCGGUGCAUCCCAGAACCGGUCGGAAUGUCCGAAGGCGGUUGUUGCUCCCUUGUUUUUCCUUGCUGCUUGUCCGUUCGCUAAAUACGCUGGGCGCCGUUCCCCAACUGUCCUUCCGAGAGCCCCUUGCCCACUUCUGUACUGUUACAGUGACGCCGCUCUGGGCGCACCGAGCCGCGCUGUGUUUCGCUGCUCUUCCUACCUAUUCUCAGUUUGUAAAGAAAUAAUCUCACAUAACACUCCUUAAUGUACUCCUCCGUAAGAUAAAUUGCAGAUAAUAUACGUCUGCUAAUUCUCUUUAUCUCCACGUCUUCUCACGCCAUGUACUAAGUAGAAAUGGUUUCAUUUAGGUGAAAAUAAUGCAGACUAGCACAUAGCACAACAAGGGCUUGUAACUAUUAAGGACUUUAUGUAACAGUCUGUAAUUCUGUGUAUCUGUCUGGUCUUUCCGGACUUGGCACUUUAGUCUCCGAGAAUAAGCCAUUUCCUGUUUAGGUAGGGUAGGACCAACCAUAACCUUGGUUCUUUCUAUGGAGUUCUGUAUGUAGCAAAUCAGCCUGUGGGAACCAUCUAUCUGUCCACCAACCUUUCACACAUAUUCUUGGGUUUGCCCGUGCAGGGACCAGUGCUGCGUAUUGUUCCCUGCCUUCCUGUACUGGACACUUAAGAGCUCACCUAAAGUUCCUCUUCCAGGAAUCAUUCUCCAGUAUACAAGGCUCUCUUCCAUUCAAUUCUUAGGCUAUUUGCGCCUUUUCCUGUGUUGCGUUUAUCUUUUUAGCCCUGUCUUCUCUUACUGUGUAGGACCUUUUGAGGGUAGAGUCUGUACCAAACUCCUAUCUUUUGUUGUAGAACCUUAACCGCUAUUUUACGGUAAACCGUACAUAUUUAAUUUUUUUUGUAAAGAUGGGAAUUGCUCUUUUAAAAUUAAUUUCUAUGAGGUCUCAAGUAGAACAUAAUUUUUAAAAAAUAAUGUGCUUGAAUAUAUAAGAUCACUACAUUUCCAACUUCCCACUCGCAACUUCAAAACUCUGAUUCUACAUAAGAGCAUUAAGGAAACGUUGUCCUCACCAGCAACAAACUGGUCAUUAUUCAUAAGAAGUUGCAGUGACUACAUAUAAUAUAUAUUUGAAAGCACUUUCUUUGAUAGCUGCUGUAGUGGAAAGACAGGAAGUUCACAGUUACAUGGAGGUUAGAUUUCUGGCCCUACAAAUUGUUAGCUGGUGACUGGACAAGUUAAGUUACUAGUAUCUCUGAUUUUUUCUCGUUUGUAGAAUGAAGAUACCAUUUCCCACCUUGGGUAGCUGAGGAUUAAAUCAGUUCUUAAACGUGAGACAUCUAGUGACACCAUGGUACUCAGGAGGUGCUCAGUAAAUACAUAUUCCCUUUGGUAUACCUGUUUAUUGCAGUUCACAAUCUAGAAUGAGCCAGGAUGUGCUAGAGACAAAGCGUGAGAGGAAAGGUAAUCAGAAGAGGUGACAGGUACCUCUCGUCUCCAAAUAAAUGAACAAGUCCUACACUAAAGAGCAUUGUGGGUCUUUCUGCUUUUCAAGAAUGUAUGGGUGUGUAUAUGUGGCGUAUUACUAAUCAUAGAGUAUAUUAAACAGAACAUUUAAAAAUGAAAAGUUUUUUUUUACUAUAAUAGCACCAACUGAAGCGUUAACAUGGACAUUAAAAAAUAAUCUUAUUUUUUUCCAAAGGCAAGUCAGGAGACGAGACGGGAAAAGGGAUAUUAAAAAGGCUCUUUAGAGGCAAUUAGGUUGCAGGCUCUUCUGUUAGCAUCUACUUAUAAACAGUACAUGAAUCCUAGUCUAAGUUCCAUUAUCUCUUGGUUGGAGUGUUUCCAUAGUGCCUUUACUGGUUUAUUUCUCUUGCUCCCUGACUGUUCCCUAGGGAUUCACCUUGACAACCAGAGGGAUCUUUUUAAAAAUGUAAAUCAGAUUGUCACUUUCUUGCUUAGUGUCCUCUAAAAGCAUCCUGUGAACCACUUACAUUUGAAUCUUAGUCGCCAUCAGGGCAUAGCAUGAUUUGGCAGCUGCCAGCUUCUAACGUUACCUCUUACUAGGUGACUGACUUUCAGCAACCUACCCCAGUCCCAUAGUCAUUUUGCCGGUUCUUGAACAAAGUGUUUCUUCCUUAGGAUGUUAUACUUACUAUUCUUUUAGCUGGACCACCCCUUCCUCUAAGUGGUCAAGGCUCUUCAUGUCUUGUCUUGUGUUUCUGCUCAAAUGUCAUCGCCUCAGGCCUUUUCUAAUUCUAAAAUAGGAACCAGCCCCUUCCUUUAUAAUCUUUUAUUCUUUAUUCUCUUUUUCUCCAUAGCAUUUAUUACUAGGUGAAGAUACACUGUUUUUUUUUUCCCACUUAUUUAUUUCCCCCCUUAGACUUGUUUGCUGCCAGCCCUGUUCUCAACAAGCGAGCAGAGGUCUUGUCUGACUUGUACACAGCUUUAUCCCCAGUGCUUAGAACUGUGCCUGGUACAUAGUAGGCUGUCAGUAAAACUUGUUGAGUAAAUGAAUAGUAUAGUUGAUUUAAAUAUUGGCUCUGGAAUCAGACAGCUAGGGUCAGAAUUCUCUGGCUCCCACCAUUUACUGAUUGAGACUGUGGGCAAGUUAAUAACUUGGUGGUGCCUCAGUUCUGCUCAUCUGUAGGAUGACUGUAAUAAUACCUACCUCACAGGAUUAUGGUGAGUAAUAAUUGAGUUAAUGUAUGUAAAGUGCUUAGAACAGGGUAAUUUUUUUUUUUUUUGAGAUGGAGUCUCGCUCUGUCGCCCACACUGGAGUGCAGUGGCACCAUCUUGGCUCACUGCAAGCUCCACCUCCUGGGUUCACGCCAUUCUCCUGCCUCAGCCUCCCGAGUAGCUGGGACUGCAGGCACCUGCCACCACGCCCGGCUAAUUUUUUGUAUUUUUAGUAGAGACGGGGUUUCACCGUGUUAUCCAGGAUGGUGUCGGUCUCCUGACCUCGUGAUCCGCCCGCCUCAGCCUCCCAAAGUGCUGGGAUUACAGGCGUGAGCCACUGGUCCCAGCCCAGAACAGGGAAAUUUUAAACCUUCUAGGAACUAUUUGAAAUUAGCUUGUUCACUUAGGAUUUUGUAUUUUGGCAUGAGAUAAAGGUGGGUUAAUUGAAUUUUUUUCUUUUUUAACAUUUUUUGAGACAGGGUCUUGCUCUGUUGCCCAAGCUGGAAUGCAGUGGUGUGAUCACGGCUCACUGCAGCCUCAACCUCCUGGGCUCAAGCCAGCCUCCCGCCUCAGGCGCUCGAGUAGCCUGCACUACAGGCAUGUGCCACCAUGCCUGGCUAGUCUUUUAAUGUUUUGUAAAGAUGGGGUCCUACUGUUUUGCCCAGGCUGGUCUCAAACUCUUGGGCUACAGUCUCCUGCCUCAUCCUCCUGCCUCAUCCUCCCAAAAUGGUGGGAUUACAAGUGUGAGCCACUGUGUCUGGCUAAAUUUUAUAUUUAUUACUUUGGUGCUGAAUUUUUGUUAGCCACCAAAAUUGUAUUUAUGGAACGCCUUUAAAAAAUACAUUUUGUGGAUGUCUAGAGCAAAUUAAAAAAUAAACUGUUGAGAAUGGUGACUGGUGUUUGGUCUUAAUGUGUAAGUCAGGUUUUUUAUUUUUCAAUCUGUAGAAGAUGCUAAGAGUGAUUAUCUCAACAACCGCCCACCAGAGUGGCUUUUAUAGAGUUCCCUUUGAAGUUCAGCUGGAGAUCUGAUUGUGGUGAUGAAAGGACUUGCUGGAGGCUUCGUGUCUUCAGACAGGAAAGUCCUUGAAGAUCCAGUUGAAAUAUGAGUCUUGUAGUAUUUGGGAAGGAAAUUUUUAUCAUCUUUAGUUGUGUUCAGUUUCUCCCUUCUUUCACUGGGUUUUUCCCCUCAGAUUAUAUUUGGUUAUUAAUUGGAACUUAAAGUAACCCAGCUGUGCUCUGUAUCUUUCUGUUCUUUUCAUAAUGAUUUAUUUUUCUUUAGCAGAUACAGAAAUAAGAGAAGAAAGAAUUGAUGGAGACAGUGACUUUGUAAUAAUAGAUAUUUUCAGCUAAUACAACUUGAAUUAUUCUCAUAAACUAAGAUUCUGCCUGUGGUAAUUGAACUUGCAUAAUACCAGUUAUUUUAAAUUCACUUGUCCUUAGUAAAAUGCUUCUUUGUAGGAUUGUUAUUUCAUUUCUCAGUCUGAACUUUAACAAGUAAUAGGAUCCUAAACCCUAGGUGUAAAUUUUUUUUUAAAAGUCAAAGGGCUGCUGCUUUGUGUAACAUUUCUUCCAAAAUUUAAUAAUUGUGAGUUAUUAUUUACUGUGUGCUAGGCUCUUUCCUAGGUGCAGUGUCUUAAUUAAUAUCUACAGCUACCGUAUAAGGUUGGCACCAUUAUAAAGAAACAGAUUUAGAGAGGUGUUGUUAUUUGGCUGGUUACACAAGAAAGGAGGCAAGAUUUCAGGCCAGUUCCCGAGGUCAUAACCGGUCUGCUGUGGGACACCUUAAAAUGACAAGGUUUUUGUUUGGAAGCUUGCCGUUAAAUUUAUCUCAUUAUUUGUGAGUGUGUGUUGUUAACUACUGGCAGCUUCAUCAUUAUUUAUGGCUAAUUUUUUGUUUUUUUUUUAGAUUUAACUACUACUACUAUACUUAAAUGCUUGUAUUAUAAGUGAAAUGUUUUAAUAGGAUGAUGACUUGCAUCGUAAUUAAUGUUUUUCUCAUAUUUAAAAGUCAUUAAAAAUAAGUCAAAGAAUCAUGUGUCUUGGUGCUUCAGCUUUGUAAAUAGUUUGAAAAGGUUUUGCAUAUAAUACAUUAGAUUUAAGAAAACAUAAAUGUCUUAAGUUUGCUCAGGGCUAAAUUGGAGGUAGCAAGUAAAUAUUUAGUAAAAGUUACUAGUGAUGUGUUUCCUGCUGACUAUGGGGCAAUUUUUUUUUUAAACUUCUAUCUUAGGUUCUGGGGUACAUAUGAAUGUUUGUUAUAUAGAUAAACUAGUGUCAUGGGGGUUUGUUGUACAGAUUGUUUCAUCACUCAGGUAUUAAGCCUGAUACACAAUAGUUACUUUUUCUGCUCGUUUCCCUCCUCCCACCCUCCACGCUUAAGUAGACUCAGUGUCUAUUGCUCCCUUCUUUGCGUUCAUGAGUUCUCAUCAUUUGGCUGCCACUUGCAAGUGAGAACAUGUGGUGUUUGGUGUUCUGUUCGUGUGUUAGUUUGCUAAGGAUAAUAGCCUACAUAGGAGAUCUUUACCUGGAUCUCCUUCAAUAAGGAGGAACACAUAGGUGGGAUGUUUUUACAUAAAUUUUAAUGGUUUCUGACAUUUCCUUGCAAGGCUUUUUUAAUUUGUAAGAAUAUCUAAAUUAUGAGUUAUUGGCUUCUCAACACCUCAGAAUGUCAGGGGUAGGAAGAAUCUUACAGACUCCAGAGGCAAUGCCAUUAUAUCUUACUGGAGGAAAGUGAGACCCCAAGAGUCAUUUGCCUGCUAAAGAGGAGAAAUAAGAUGAGACCCUAGGUUUUCCCCCCAAGGCCAUUUUUUCCCCCUGCUACACCAAACUGUUCCCUGCAUUACUGAGGGAAAGACCAGCAACACUUAGUAUCUCAUAUUCAAGAGGGUGGAAAAUAAAACGAUAUGUUCUUGUAAAAUUACGAUUUAAAGUCUUGAUUUUAUCAUUGGAACAUAAUAGAAAAAAAUUUUGUCCUCUAUUAUAAUGCAGUUGAAAAUGAUACUUUCUCAUAUAGGCAGGAGACUGCCUUAUCCACAUAGGAUGCUUUGAGAAACCUUUUAAAGACUAGUCGGGUCCCAUGGCUUUGUGCUUGAAUUAAAAUAUUAGGUAGUGAUGGGCAAAAAAAGUUGGUUGUGAUGUGAGUAGUUCGUAUUCAAACUCAUAGCCUAUUAAGCAAAGUGUUGCUUACUGACCUCAGUCAUUCCUGAUCAUACCCAAGGCUAAAAUGAACUUUUUGGAGGUUUAGUCACAAAAUAAUGGCUGCAUCUUACAUUCUCUAAGCUCCAUCAUUUCUACAUUUGCUAUUUCUAGGAAUGGACUUAAUGCAUUUUUAUCUUUUAGGCACUGGUCUGAGUUAUGUAGUUGAAACUACUUAGAUUUUUUGCUCUUUUAAAUGGUUUUCAUUAAGUUCUGUAUUUUACUCAUAAUAAAUUCAAUUUCUUGAUGACUCCUUAGCUUUUUAUUUUAAGCCUUUUUUUUUAAAGCAUUUAACCUGGACAGUUCUGAACUUUACAAAUGUUUUAACAAUUUCUUCUUCAAUAUCUUAAAGACCGUAACAAAAAAAAAAUUUUUUUUUUUUUUUUUGAAACGGAGUUUUGCCCUUGUCGCCCAGGCUGGAGUGCUAUGGCAUGAUCUUGGUUCACUGCAACCUCCUCCUCCCAGGUUCAAGCGAUUGUCCUGCCUCAGCCUCCCAAGUGGUUGAGAUUACAGGCACCUGCCACCACGCCCAGCUGGGUUUUGUAUUUUUAGUAGAGACGGGGUUUCACCAUGUUGGCCAGGCUGGUCUCGAACUCCUGACCUCAGGUGAUCCCGCCUGCCUCGGCCUCCCAAAGUGUAAAUUUUUUAAUACAGAAUUUUUUCUCAUGAUAAUCUUCUCUGUGUCAUUCCAAUUUUAGUGUAUGUGCAGCCGAAGCAAACACAACGUUUUAUAUCUUAAAGAGUGCUUUUACCUAACUUUUUUCUCAUUUAAUUCUCUUAAGAGUCCUGGGAAGAGAAGUAAGGCAGCAUAUCCUAUUUUAUAGCUGUAGUGUAAUUUGGGCACCUGCUACCCAGAGUUAGGUAAGGCAUCGUAAGUUAAGGGUACAGUCUGCAAGACUCUCCUCACUUCUUAUAUUAGCUACAAACUCCAGGACUUGCAGGUUAUCCACACUCUGACCAACUGGCUACAACUUUCGGAGUUCCCACUACACCUCACGUUUGAUAAUUUGGUAGAAUGACUCGCAGACCUCAGGAAAGUGCUGUUCUUGGAAUUACAGUUAUGAUACAAAUCAGGACCAGCCAAUUAAAGAGACACAUAGAACAAGAUCUGGGAGGGUCCCAAACAUGAAGCUUCCAUGUCCUCAGGACGUGUCAUCCUUCCAGUACAGCAGUGAAUGAUUGCCAGCCAGGAAACCUCACUUACUCUACAGCAUCUGGAGUUUUUAUGGGACUUUUAUUACAUAGGUAUGAUUGAACUCAGUCCCCAGUCCCCUUCUCCCUGGAGGUCAAGUUGUUAGGCUGAUGUCAGGUUGCUCAAAGCCCAACCCACUAUUCACAUGGUUGGCAUUUCCAGCAUGGCCAGGCCCCAUCCUGAAACUAGGGGCCUACUGGGAGUCACCCUGUUAAUAGAAACUCAGCUGUGGGCCAAGGAGGACCCAUUAUGGAUUCAUGGAUAACAAAGACACUCCUAUCAGUUGGGAGACUCCAAGAGUAGAGUUUUCCAGGAAUCAGACAAUGGCCAGUCAAAUUUUUUUGUUUUUGUUUUUUUAGGGACGGGGUCUCACUGUGUCACAGUGGUGCUAUCAUAGCUCACUGUAGCCUCCAGCUUUCAGGCCAAAGUGAUCCUCCUGCCUCAGCCUCCCCAGUAGCUAGGACUACAGGCACACACCACCGCACCUGGCUAAUUUAAAUUUUUGUGUGUGUGUGUGUGUAGGGAUCUCCCCAUGUUGCCCAGGCUGGUUUCAGACUCCUGGCCUCAAGUGAUCCUCCUGCCUUGGCCUCCCAGAGUGCUGGUAUACAGGCAUGUGCCACUGUGCCUGGGCCCCAAAUUCUUUAUUACACAAUGCUGGCUAAAGAAGUGAGAACAGACACUUGCUCAAUUUAUGACAGCUAAAACUAGUAGUAGUGAUAGUAACCCAGUUACCUCUGUUGUAUUAAAAAUUGGAACAGGUUGCAUUUGAAUAUGGAUAGAAGGAUUGCCUUCUGUUGAGAAUUACUACAUAACAUUUUUUUUAUUGAUACAAUAUAAUUUAAAACUUGGGUUAUUCACUUGAGUUAAAUGUUUUAAUUACAUAAAUUUUGUAGCUUGGGUUAUAAACUGUAUACUUGAUACUUUAAAGCUUAAUAAUUGGCUGUAAAAAAUCUGAAUUUUGGUAUUGGUCUUGAAUUUGUACUUUUAGAUGUACGUAAUUAUUCAUUAGUUAUUUGGAAGAAGAAAUUAUGAAGUGAGAUAUUUAUGGGUAGGGUGGAGGCAUUGAUAAUCUAUUUGUGUUAGGGUUGUAAAAUGUUUCAGUAACUUAAUUGCUGUUUUGAAUUUUAGCACUUGAGUCAAAGUUACUAACACUUCAAGUUUACUGUGUUGGAGGUUAAUAUUCUUUUGCAUAUUAUUUAUGCCUAAUCUUAUUUCAGAUUGUCACUUGAAGAUUAUAUUGAAUUAUCUUGGAACUCACUGUUCCUCAGAGAUUAUAGUGUGCUAAAUUGUUACAUUGAAUAAGACUUCUGGUGUCUUGAAGAAUGUAGCAUGUUGUAAUGUUUUUGUUUUUUUAAAAGUAUAUAAUUUUAAAUAUAUUCUUGGUGUAAGCAAGGGAAAAUUCCAGAAGCAGUGACAACUUCUGCUUCCUUUAUGUUUAUUUGGAAUUACAUUUAAUAGAAGCAUUUGUGAGAAAAGGGAUUUGUGAAUGCUGGAACUGAUAGCAGGUCCAGAAAAAAAGAGUUUGACUAUAUUUUUGAAUUGCAGUUGCUCUGAGGGAUUUGUUUUUAGUUAUGUGUCAUUGUUUAUGCCAGUUACCUUGUGAGUUCAGAGAUCUAAUGACUUGUGUGGGUGGAAUGCACAAGGUGAGGACUUCUGCUAAGAUUUAUACGUUAUGGUGUAGGCUAGGCUCAGGAGCCAGAAACUCUCCCACCCAAUUUACACUUGCUUAAAACUUACAAAGUAAGGUUUAAACUUCUUAGUAUGAUAUAUUCAAGGCCUUCUGUUAUAUUUCUCCACCUACCUUAGUUUGUCUACCUCUACAUCUGGCCAUGUUCCUACAUACUGGUAAGUUCUAGAAUGUUGUCCUAAACAUCUUUUUGUAUUUUUUAUGAGGCAGAGUCUUGCUCUAUAGUCUAGGCCUGAGUGCAGUGACGUGAUGAUGGCUCACUACAGUCUUAACCUCCCAGGCUCAAGCAGUUCUCCCAUCCCACUCUCCCAAGUAGCUGUGGCCAUGGGCGUGCACCACCAUGACUGGCUAAUUAAAAACAAAUUUUUUGUGGAGACAAGGGUCUCACUUCAUUGCCCAGGCUGAUCUCGAAUUCCUGGGCUUGAGCAGUCCUCCUGCCGUAACCCCGCAAAGUGCUGAGAUACAGGUGUGAGCCACUGCACUCGGCCCUUUUAUGUUUUUAAUUAUGAAUUUUUCUUCUUCCUGAAAUCUUUGCCUUCAUGUCACCCCUUCCCACCUACCUUCUAUCCUACCUUCUAUCCUGUAAAAUCCUACUGAUUGUUCUUAGUUCAGAUCUACCUCUCAGUGAUGCUUUCUUGGGUGUCUUCUCGAACAUGAGAUUUAUGGCUGUUUUCUCUGUGCAUUUAUUGCAUUCCAUUAGUGCCUAUAAUGCAGGAUCUUGUAUUAUUAUUAUUAUUAUUAUUAUUUUUACUUUUUUGGUCUUGUUCUGUCUCCCAGGCCAAGUGCAGUGGUUCACUGCAGCCUUGACCUUCCAGGCUCAAGCGAUCCUCCCACCUCAGCCUCCUGACUACAGAAGCUCCACCAUGAGGCGAGGUGGAUGGAGGAAGCGAGCUGAAAAUGAUGGCUGGGAAACAUGGGGUGGGUAUAUGGCUGCCAAGGUCCAGAAAUUGGAGGAACAGUUUCGAUCAGAUGCUGCUAUGCAGAAGGAUGGGACUUCAUCUACAAUUUUUAGUGGAGUUGCCAUCUAUGUUAAUGGAUACACAGAUCCUUCCGCUGAGGAAUUGAGAAAACUAAUGAUGUUGCAUGGAGGUCAAUACCAUGUAUAUUAUUCCAGAUCUAAAACAACACAUAUUAUUGCCACAAAUCUUCCCAAUGCCAAAAUUAAAGAAUUAAAGGGGGAAAAAGUAAUUCGACCAGAAUGGAUUGUGGAAAGCAUCAAAGCUGGACGACUCCUCUCCUACAUUCCAUAUCAGCUGUACACCAAGCAGUCCAGUGUGCAGAAAGGUCUCAGCUUUAAUCCUGUAUGCAGACCUGAGGAUCCUCUGCCAGGUCCAAGCAAUAUAGCCAAACAGCUCAACAACAGGGUAAAUCACAUCGUUAAGAAGAUUGAAACGGAAAAUGAAGUCAAAGUCAAUGGCAUGAACAGUUGGAAUGAAGAAGAUGAAAAUAAUGAUUUUAGUUUUGUGGAUCUGGAGCAGACCUCUCCGGGAAGGAAACAGAAUGGAAUUCCGCAUCCCAGAGGGAGCACUGCCAUUUUUAAUGGACACACUCCUAGCUCUAAUGGUGCCUUAAAGACACAGGAUUGCUUGGUGCCCAUGGUCAACAGUGUUGCCAGCAGGCUUUCUCCAGCCUUUUCCCAGGAGGAGGAUAAGGCUGAGAAGAGCAGCACUGAUUUCAGAGACUGCACUCUGCAGCAGUUGCAGCAAAGCACCAGAAACACAGAUGCUUUGCGGAAUCCACACAGAACUAAUUCUUUCUCAUUAUCACCUUUGCACAGUAACACUAAAAUCAAUGGUGCUCACCACUCCACUGUUCAGGGGCCUUCAAGCACAAAAAGCACUUCUUCAGUAUCUACGUUUAGCAAGGCAGCACCUUCAGUGCCAUCCAAACCUUCAGACUGCAAUUUUAUUUCAAACUUCUAUUCUCAUUCAAGACUGCAUCACAUAUCAAUGUGGAAGUGUGAAUUGACUGAGUUUGUCAAUACCCUACAAAGACAAAGUAAUGGUAUCUUUCCAGGAAGGGAAAAGUUAAAAAAAAUGAAAACAGGCAGGUCUGCACUUGUUGUAACUGACACAGGAGAUAUGUCAGUAUUGAAUUCUCCCAGACAUCAGAGCUGUAUAAUGCAUGUUGAUAUGGAUUGCUUCUUUGUAUCAGUGGGUAUACGAAAUAGACCAGAUCUCAAAGGAAAACCAGUGGCUGUUACAAGUAACAGAGGCACAGGAAGGGCACCUUUACGUCCUGGCGCUAACCCCCAGCUGGAGUGGCAGUAUUACCAGAAUAAAAUCCUGAAAGGCAAAGCAGCAGAUAUACCAGAUUCAUCAUUGUGGGAGAAUCCAGAUUCUGCGCAAGCAAAUGGAAUUGAUUCUGUUUUGUCAAGGGCUGAAAUUGCAUCUUGUAGUUAUGAGGCCAGGUCCCUCAAAGUUCUGGAACCCUGGCUCCUGCCCAGAGUGAUGUCCUACCAUGUACAAUGCUGUUGGCAUCUCAACCACUGUGGAGCCACUUCAGGAGCAUGGAAUUGGCAACUUGGCAUUAAGAACGGAAUGUUUUUUGGGCAUGCUAAACAACUAUGUCCUAAUCUUCAAGCUGUUCCAUACGAUUUUCAUGCAUAUAAGGAAGUCGCACAAACAUUGUAUGAAACAUUGGCAAGCUACACUCAUAACAUUGAAGCUGUCAGUUGUGAUGAAGCGCUGGUAGACAUUACCGAAAUCCUUGCAGAGACCAAACUUACUCCUGAUGAAUUUGCAAAUGCUGUUCGUAUGGAAAUCAAAGACCAGACGAAAUGUGCUGCCUCUGUUGGAAUUGGUUCUAAUAUUCUCCUGGCUAGAAUGGCAACUAGAAAAGCAAAACCAGAUGGGCAGUACCACCUAAAACCAGAAGAAGUAGAUGAUUUUAUCAGAGGCCAGCUAGUGACCAAUCUACCAGGAGUUGGACAUUCAAUGGAAUCUAAGUUGGCAUCUUUGGGAAUUAAAACUUGUGGAGACUUGCAGUAUAUGACCAUGGCAAAACUCCAAAAAGAAUUUGGUCCCAAAACAGGUCAGAUGCUUUAUAGGUUCUGCCGUGGCUUGGAUGAUAGACCAGUUCGAACUGAAAAGGAAAGAAAAUCUGUUUCAGCUGAGAUCAACUAUGGAAUAAGGUUUACUCAGCCAAAAGAGGCAGAAGCUUUUCUUCUGAGUCUUUCAGAAGAAAUUCAAAGAAGACUAGAAGCCACUGGCAUGAAGGGUAAACGUCUAACUCUCAAAAUCAUGGUACGAAAGCCUGGGGCUCCUGUAGAAACUGCAAAAUUUGGAGGCCAUGGAAUUUGUGAUAACAUUGCCAGGACUGUAACUCUUGACCAGGCAACAGAUAAUGCAAAAAUAAUUGGAAAGGCGAUGCUAAACAUGUUUCAUACAAUGAAACUAAAUAUAUCAGAUAUGAGAGGGGUUGGGAUUCACGUGAAUCAGUUGGUUCCAACUAAUCUGAACCCUUCCACAUGUCCCAGUCGCCCAUCAGUUCAGUCAAGCCACUUUCCUAGUGGGUCAUACUCUGUCCGUGAUGUCUUCCAAGUUCAGAAAGCUAAGAAAUCCACCGAAGAGGAGCACAAAGAAGUAUUUCGGGCUGCUGUGGAUCUGGAAAUAUCAUCUGCUUCUAGAACUUGCACUUUCUUGCCACCUUUUCCUGCACAUCUGCCGACCAGUCCUGAUACUAACAAGGCUGAGUCUUCAGGGAAAUGGAAUGGUCUACAUACUCCUGUCAGUGUGCAGUCGAGACUUAACCUGAGUAUAGAGGUCCCGUCACCUUCCCAGCUGGAUCAGUCUGUUUUAGAAGCACUUCCACCUGAUCUCCGGGAACAAGUAGAGCAAGUCUGUGCUGUCCAGCAAGCAGAGUCACAUGGCGACAAAAAGAAAGAACCAGUAAAUGGCUGUAAUACAGGAAUUUUGCCACAACCAGUUGGGACAGUCUUGUUGCAAAUACCAGAACCUCAAGAAUCGAACAGUGACGCAGGAAUAAAUUUAAUAGCCCUUCCAGCAUUUUCACAGGUGGACCCUGAGGUAUUUGCUGCCCUUCCUGCUGAACUUCAGAGGGAGCUGAAAGCAGCGUAUGAUCAAAGACAAAGGCAGGGCGAGAACAGCACUCACCAGCAGUCAGCCAGCGCAUCUGUGCCAAAGAAUCCUUUACUUCAUCUAAAGGCAGCAGUGAAAGAAAAGAAAAGAAACAAGAAGAAAAAAACCAUUGGUUCACCAAAAAGGAUUCAGAGUCCUUUGAAUAACAAGCUGCUUAACAGUCCUGCAAAAACUCUGCCAGGGGCCUGUGGCAGUCCCCAGAAGUUAAUUGAUGGGUUUCUAAAACAUGAAGGACCUCCUGCAGAGAAACCCCUGGAAGAACUCUCUGCUUCUACUUCAGGUGUGCCAGGCCUUUCUAGUUUGCAGUCUGACCCAGCUGGCUGUGUGAGACCUCCAGCACCCAAUCUAGCUGGAGCUGUUGAAUUCAAUGAUGUGAAGACCUUGCUCAGAGAAUGGAUAACUACAAUUUCAGAUCCAAUGGAAGAAGACAUUCUCCAAGUUGUGAAAUACUGUACUGAUCUAAUAGAAGAAAAAGAUUUGGAAAAACUGGAUCUAGUUAUAAAAUACAUGAAAAGGCUGAUGCAGCAAUCGGUGGAAUCGGUUUGGAAUAUGGCAUUUGACUUUAUUCUUGACAAUGUCCAGGUGGUUUUACAACAAACUUAUGGAAGCACAUUAAAAGUUACAUAAAUAUUACCAGAGAGCCUGAUGCUCUCUGAUAGCUGUGCCAUAAGUGCUUGUGAGGUAUUUGCAAAGUGCAUGAUAGUAAUGCUCGGAGUUUUUAUAAUUUUAAAUUUCUUUUAAAGCAAGUGUUUUGUACAUUUCUUUUCAAAAAGUGCCAAAUUUGUCAGUAUUGCAUGUAAAUAAUUGUGUUAAUUAUUUUACUGUAGCAUAGAUUCUAUUUACAAAAUGUUUGUUUAUAAAGUUUUAUGGAUUUUUACAGUGAAGUGUUUACAGUUGUUUAAUAAAGAACUGUAUGUAUAUUUUGUACAGGCUCCUUUUUGUGAAUCCUUAAAAACUCAACUCUAGGAAGCAACUACUGUUUAUUAUACUAAAAGGCUGAAAAACCUCCAGGCCAGACUGCUAAGCUCUGAAAUUCCUGAGAGGUCUCAGACCGGGAUUCUACUUGUUCCAAGAAAGGGUAAAGCUUCUAAACCAUCUUAUUCUUGUCUCCAAGCAUGAACACAGGAGCAUGUUAAGAAAAUCUUUACUACUUCUUCCAUGCGGAGAAAUCUACAUAUUUUGAAUUAGAAACACCCUCACACCCACUUGAAGAUUUUUUUCCUGGGAACAUUAUGUCCCGUAGAUCAGAGGUGGUGUUGUCUUUUUGCUUCUACUGGCCAUUGAGAAACUUUGAUGAUAAAAAAGAACGGUAUAGAUUUUUCAAACGUAUAUAAAAUAUUUUUAUGUUAUAUGUUAUGCCAUAACUUUAAAAUAAAAAUAGUUUAAAAUUC